CGAAGUCACAUCCUGAUAAAUUGAAAAUAUAGAAGAUAAAAAAUGCAUUUAAUAUUAUGUCACCUACAAAACAUCAGAGUUUAGCCUAGCCUACCCUAAACCCGCCCUGAACACGUACCUUCCCCUACAGUUGGGCAAAAUCGUCCAACAGAAAACCUAUUUUAUAAUAAAGUGUUGACUCUCUCCUGUAGUUUAUUGAAUACUGAACUGAAAGUGACAAUCAGAAUGGCGGUGUGGAUCCUCCUCAGCAAUGUGCACAGCUGAAAGCACCGCCGCAAAGGAGAAAAAUUGUACGUGGAGCUGUUACCGGAUGGAGUUGUCCACGUUCUAGGCGUGUUGAACAGAGAAUUGAAUGAAACGCACAAAGUAACAAAAGAACAAAGCAACGAAAGACAAAAACACAAAAAAACGGAGUAAGGAAAGCACAGGUUUAUUGAAGACAAUUCACAGACUGGGAGCGGGGCUCCAGCAAGAGGCCCAAGAGCUUCCUCAAUUAGGGUUUUUAUUAAAAGGAACCCGGCAAUACCCCUCGGUGUCUUUGACAGGCCUCCCAUUGGCUACACCCCGUGAAGGACUGACCUGCGACCAGUCAGAGGCUGACGUGGAGACUUGGCCCACCGUCCGUCAGAGGCUGGAGUGGAGGCUUGGCCCACCAUCCAUCAGAGGCUGGAGUGGAGACUUGGCCCACCGUCCAUCAGAGGCUGGAGUGGAGGCUUGGCCCACGGUCAAUCAGAGGUUGGAGUGGAGGCUUGGCCCACCGUCCAUCAGAGGCUGGAAUGGAGGCUUGGCCCACCGUCCAUCAGAGGCUGGAGUGGAGGCUUGGCCCACGGUCAAUCAGAGGUUGGAGUGGAGGCGUGGCCCACCGUCCAUCAGAGGCUGGAAUGGAGGCUUGGCCCACCGUCCAUCAGAGGCUGGAAUGGAGGCUUGGCCCACCGUCCAUCAGAGGCUGGAGUGGAGGCUUGGCCCACCGUCCAUCAGAGGCUGGAGUGGAGACUUGGCCCACCGUCCAUCAGAGGCUGGAGUGGAGGCUUGGCCCACCAUCCAUCAGAGGCUGGAGUGGAGACUUGGCCCACCGUCCAUCAGAGGCUGGAAUGGAGGCUUGGCCCACCGUCCAUCAGAGGUUGGAGUGGAGGCUUGGCCCACGGUCAAUCAGAGGCUGGAAUGGAGGCUUGGCCCACCGUCCAUCAGAGGCUGGAGUGGAGGCUUGGCCCACCGUCCAUCAGAGGCUGGAGUGGAGACUUGGCCCACCGUCCAUCAGAGGCUGGAGUGGAGGCUUGGCCCACGGUCAAUCAGAGGCUGGAGUGGAGACUUGGCCCACCGUCCAUCAGAGGCUGGAAUGGAGGCUUGGCCCACCGUCCAUCAGAGGCUGGAGUGGAGGCUUGGCCCACCGUCCAUCAGAGGCUGGAGUGGAGACUUGGCCCACCGUCCAUCAGAGGCUGGAGUGGAGGCUUGGCCCACCGUCCAUCAGAGGCUGGAGUGGAGACUUGGCCCACCGUCCAUCAGAGGCUGGAGUGGAGGCUUGGCCCACCGUCCAUCAGAGGUUGGAGUGGAGGCUUGGCCCACGGUCAAUCAGAGGCUGGAGUGGAGGCUUGGCCCACCGUCCAUCAGAGGCUGGAGUGGAGGCUUGGCCCACCAUCCAUCAGAGGCUGGAGUGGAGACUUGGCCCACCGUCCAUCAGAGGCUGGAAUGGAGGCUUGGCCCACCGUCCAUCAGAGGCUGGAGUGGAGGCUUGGCCCACCGUCCAUCAGAGGCUGGAGUGGAGACUUGGCCCACUGUCCAUCAGAGGCUGGAGUGGAGACUUGGCCCACCGUCCAUCAGAGACUGGAGUGGAGGCUUGGCCCACCAUCCAUCAGAGGCUGGAGUGGAGACUUGGCCCACGGUCCAUCAGAGGCUGGAGUGGAGACUUGGCCCACCGUCCAUCAGAGGCUGGAGUGGAGACUUGGCCCACGGUCAAUCAGAGGCUGGAGUGGAGGCUUGGCCCACCGUCCAUCAGAGGCUGGAGUGGAGACUUGGCCCACGGUCAAUCAGAGGCUGGAGUGGAGGCUUGGCCCACCGUCCAUCAGAGGCUGGAGUGGAGACUUGGCCCACCGUCCAUCAGAGGCUGGAGUGGAGGCUUGGCCCACCGUCCAUCAGAGGCUGGAGUGGAGGCUUGGCCCACCAUCCAUCAGAGGCUGGAGUGGAGACUUGGCCCACGGUCCAUCAGAGGCUGGAGUGGAGACUUGGCCCACCGUCCAUCAGAGGCUGGAGUGGAGACUUGGCCCACGGUCCAUCAGAGGCUGGAGUGGAGGCUUGGCCCACCAUCCAUCAGAGGCUGGAGUGGAGACUUGGCCCACGGUCCAUCAGAGGCUGGAGUGGAGACUUGGCCCACCGUCCAUCAGAGGCUGGAGUGGAGACUUGGCCCACGGUCAAUCAGAGGCUGGAGUGGAGGCUUGGCCCACCGUCCAUCAGAGGCUGGAGUGGAGGCUUCUGUCUCGUUAUCACAGGAGUGAGGAUGUGGCCUGUGUGCUGCCUAAUCUUGCCUAGAACUGGCUGCAAGUGCGGUUCUUUUGCUUCUACCUUAACCCCUGGUUACCCUAAUUCCCUUGUAGUAGGACGAGCCACAGACGAAACCUCUCAGACACCGAGUUGUAGAAGGAAGGGCUUUAUUCAGCUGGGAGCAUUGGCAAGCUACUGCCUUGAAAUCCGAGCUCCACGAGUGAGCAAUUCCUGUCCCUUUUAAGGGCUCACAACUCUAAGGAUUUCACAUGAAAGGGUCGUGAUUGAUUUGAGCAAGCAAGGGGUACGUGACAGGGGCUGCAUGCACCGGUGGUCAGAGAGAAACAGAACAGGGCAGGGAGUUUCACAAUGUUGUUCUAUACAAUGUCUGGAAUCUAUGAAUAACAUCGGUUUUUAAGUUAUCAGUUGAUUUUUAACUACUGGGUUUAGGCCAGGCAGGCCCAGGCCUGGUUUCGGGCCUGGCGCCGGGCUGCCUGUCUUUGGUUUUACUUCCUUGUUGUUUUUUUUUUAAAACAGGUAUUGAGUAUAAAACAAUAUAAAACAAUAUGAGAGGGUCUCUCUCUUCCCUCACCCUAUUCUCCUGCCUCAGAGCCCUCAGAAGUAGGGGAUGGUCCCUAACAUUGAUUACAACCCCUAGUCCGUAUAAUAUAUCUUCAGAGCUUGUUCACCCUGCAUGGCUGCAAACGUUUUCUCUUUUCUUUUUAUGACCUGAACCGGGGAGCCCAGGAAUUCUGUACUCUUCAAGAGAACUCUUUCCUCUUCAGUAGUUUCUUCCUUCCCACUUUGUGAACCAGGAAGACCUUGAAAAUGGGAACAUGCUUCUUGUUUUCACUUUCCUUCUUUUUACCAAUUUCUCUGCCUCAUUCACUGACGAAUUGGCUGCUAUCCCACACACCUCCUCUCCUACUGACAUUCUGAAAUCUUUGUGAGUUCAGCCUCCGGACACACAAUCUCUUAUUUGUAGAGUUGGGUCUCACUAUGUUGCCCAGGCUGGUCUCAAAUUCCUGGUCUCAAGAAAUCCUCCUGCCUCAGCCUUCCAGAGUGCUGGGAUUACAGGCGUGAGUUACUGUGCGUGCUCACGGUGCCUGGCCCGGGUUCCUUUUCUGCCAGCUUGGAAGGGCAACCCCAUGACUGAAUGUUAUUCUGAGGGUGGCUCCGCAUUUGCAUCCUUGUUACAGUGCAUCCACUUGAAACACUGCACAUCUGAACUGGGACUGUUAACACACAUGCUGAUACAGUGUGGGGUGCCAGGAAGUGUCUGCUGAUAUUUAUGGCAAAAAAAAAAAAUCUGUUUUGUUUACUUAGUGUAUCAAAAGAAAGUCUGGGGUGAACAGUAGUAUUUUUUUUUAAGCAGCUGUGAAAAAAAGUUGGAGAUCUCCAAAAAAAAAAAAAAAGGUGAUUUCAUAGAAAAGUAUAGGAUUCGGUGUGGGUGAGGUUGCUUCAAGUUGGUUUGGUACAAGAACUUUCUAGCCAUUCCUUAUCUGUUUAGAAGUGAAUGAUCCACCCACCGCCAGGAUGGCUCAUCAAACAAUGGAACCAUUUGCCCUUAUGGCGCACAGCUGUAAUAUCCAAUCAUCUCCAGGUGCCAAGCAUGUCCUCUCAUUUCAUUCUCAACACGAUAACGAGCGGAGGGCGGGGACCAUUUCAAAGACAAAACGUGGACACCGUUUUUAUAGACAAUGAUGUUUGGACUAAAUGAAUGCCAUGACCUGACUUUCUCAACAGUCUGAAGCUAAAUAGAAACAAGCAGAAGUCUCAUCUCAAGCCUGCCAGGCCCCAUCCUGUAGGCACAUGUGAAAUGUAAAAACUUGACCCAUUGUACUAGUAGGUGGAGCUGCCAUUAUUUGAGUCAUUGAAUAGUGUUGAGACAGAAUUGGGUUGACACUGCCAACUCCUAAAAUUAGAAUCUAGACAUUGCAGGUACAUCACUCACAGCUCCAACGAAUGCCUCUGCCUUCAUAGAGUAGCUUUCUGACUUCUGUUUAACAUUUUUUUUGGAAUAAAGUCUUGGAAAUAAGCCCAUAUAGUCAGACAUGAUGGCUGAUGCCUGUAAUCCUAGCACUUUAAGAAGCUGAGGCUGGUGGAUUGCUUGGGUCCAGGAGUUAAAGACCAGCCUGGGCAACAUGGUGAAACUCGGUGUCUACAAAAACAUACAAAACAAUUAGCCAGGCCUGGUGGUGCACACCUGUGGUCGCAGCUACUGGGGAAGCUGAGGUGAGAGGAUUGCUUGAGCCUGAGAGGUGGAGGCUGCAGUGAGCUAUGAUUGUGCAACUGUGCUUCAGCCUGGGCAACAGAGCAAGACCCUGUCUGAAAAAAAGAAAAAGAAAAAGAAAAAAAAAUUAGCCUAUAUAGGGGAAGGGGAAGAAAAAAGAGCUCAGUGUGGAUCACAGCAGAGUCAGCCAGGUUGAUGGCUGUGGCUUGCCCAUGAGUACUGGUAGUUGAGAUGAGGAGAGCUGGUCAGAUUCUGAACUUGUUUUCAAGUUUUAAGAGAAUCCUCUUUUUUUUUCAUGGUCUUAUUGAGGUACAGUUGAUAUAAAAUAAAUAACUCAUAUCCAAAGGGCCCAAUUUAAUAAAGUUUGGAAUACUACUCAGCAGUAAAAAGAAAUCAUUGAUAACACCCAAGAACAUGGAUGAAUCUCAAAAUAGUUACGAAGGUGAAAGGGGACAGCCAGAAAAAAAGUGCAUCUGGUAUGAGUCUAUCAAUAUAAAAUUCUAGAAAAUUCUAUUACUAGGCUGGGCACAGUGGCUGACACAUGUAAUCUCAGCACUUUGGGAGGCAAAAGCAGGUGGAUUGCUUGAGCCCAGGAGUUCAAGAUCAGCCUAGGCAAUGUAGUGAGACCCAUCUCUACAAAAAGUAGAAAAAAUUAGCCGGACAUAGUGGUCCCAGCCACCUGGGGGGGCUGAGGUAGGAGGUUCACUUAAGGCUGAGAAGUUGAGGCUGCAGUGAGCCGUGAUCAUACCACUGCACUGCAGCCUGGGCAACAGAGCAAGACACUGUCUCAAAAAAAAAGAAAAGAAAAAAAGAAAGAAAAAAGAAAAUUCUGUCCGUGAUCUGUAAUGACACAGAGAACACCAGUGGUUGUCCAGGGAUGGAGCUGUGGGAGGGACAGAUGAUGAAGAGCCUGGGGAAGCGUUGGAGGAUGGUGGGGAUGUUCAGCUUCUUGAUGACGGCAAUGACUUCAUGAGUAUGUACAAAUGUCAGAACUUGGACUCUGGACAUGCAGGCACAGGAACCAGCUAGAGGAGCUGCUGCACAGCAGUGUAAAUGCACCAAAUGCUGCUAAACUGUACAGAUAAAACAGUUAAUUUUAUGUCACGUGAAAUUCAUGUCAAUAAACACAUUAAUUAAGGUA